GCUGUACUUUUCUGGGUGUGUGUUAGGGAGGCUAUGUUCCUGACCCUCCCCCUCUGGGGUGAGAAGGGGUCCCCGCCAUGUCCUCGGGGUUGGUAGGAGGAGAGGAUUGGAGCUGUUUUCUCCUUGAUGCCAAGAUACGCCAAGCUAGGAGCAUUCUGCCCUUUCCACAGUCAUCCACCGAGAACAGGCCUGCAGGACGGGACAAGGAUCAGAGCCUUCCUGCAACCCCGGCCACUGCCUGCUGUCUGUGGGCCUGGACUGUGCGGGCAACUGUGCUUGGCCCGAGUGACAAGGAGGUGGGAGAGGGUAGCAGCAUGGGCUACGCGGUUGGCUGCCCUCAGUCCCCCUGCUGCUGAAGCUGCCCUGCCCAUGCCCACCCAGGCCGUGGGGCCAGGGGCCUGCCAGGGCUAGGAGUGGGCCUGCCGUUCAUGGGUCUCUAGGGAUUUCCGAGAUGCCUGGGAAGAGAGGCUUGGGCUGGUGGUGGGCCCGGCUGCCCCUUUGCCUGCUCCUCAGCCUUUACGGCCCCUGGAUGCCUUCCUCCCUGGGAAAGCCCAAAGGCCACCCUCACAUGAAUUCCAUCCGCAUAGAUGGGGACAUCACACUGGGAGGCCUGUUCCCGGUGCAUGGCCGGGGCUCAGAGGGCAAGCCCUGUGGAGAACUUAAGAAGGAAAAGGGCAUCCACCGGCUGGAGGCCAUGCUGUUCGCCCUGGAUCGCAUCAACAACGACCCGGACCUGCUGCCUAACAUCACGCUGGGCGCCCGCAUUCUGGACACCUGCUCCAGGGACACCCAUGCCCUCGAGCAGUCGCUGACCUUUGUGCAGGCGCUCAUCGAGAAGGAUGGCACAGAGGUCCGCUGUGGCAGUGGCGGCCCACCCAUCAUCACCAAGCCUGAACGUGUGGUGGGUGUCAUCGGUGCUUCAGGGAGCUCGGUCUCCAUCAUGGUGGCCAACAUCCUUCGCCUCUUCAAGAUACCCCAGAUCAGCUACGCCUCCACAGCGCCAGACCUGAGUGACAACAGCCGCUACGACUUCUUCUCCCGCGUGGUGCCCUCGGACACGUACCAGGCCCAGGCCAUGGUGGACAUCGUCCGUGCCCUCAAGUGGAACUAUGUGUCCACAGUGGCCUCGGAGGGCAGCUAUGGUGAGAGCGGUGUGGAGGCCUUCAUCCAGAAGUCCCGUGAGGACGGGGGCGUGUGCAUCGCCCAGUCGGUGAAGAUACCACGGGAGCCCAAGGCAGGCGAGUUCGACAAGAUCAUCCGCCGCCUCCUGGAGACUUCGAACGCCAGGGCAGUCAUCAUCUUUGCCAACGAGGAUGACAUCAGGCGUGUGCUGGAGGCAGCACGAAGGGCCAACCAGACAGGCCAUUUCUUCUGGAUGGGCUCUGACAGCUGGGGCUCCAAGAUUGCACCUGUGCUGCACCUGGAGGAGGUGGCUGAGGGUGCUGUCACGAUCCUCCCCAAGAGGAUGUCCGUACGAGGCUUCGACCGCUACUUCUCCAGCCGCACGCUGGACAACAACCGGCGCAACAUCUGGUUUGCCGAGUUCUGGGAGGACAACUUCCACUGCAAGCUGAGCCGCCACGCCCUCAAGAAGGGCAGCCACGUCAAGAAGUGCACCAACCGUGAGCGAAUUGGGCAGGAUUCAGCUUAUGAGCAGGAGGGGAAGGUGCAGUUUGUGAUCGAUGCCGUGUACGCCAUGGGCCACGCGCUGCACGCCAUGCACCGUGACCUGUGUCCCGGCCGCGUGGGGCUCUGCCCGCGCAUGGACCCUGUAGAUGGCACCCAGCUGCUUAAGUACAUCCGAAACGUCAACUUCUCAGGCAUCGCAGGGAACCCUGUGACCUUCAAUGAGAAUGGAGAUGCGCCUGGGCGCUAUGACAUCUACCAAUACCAGCUGCGCAACGAUUCUGCCGAGUACAAGGUCAUUGGCUCCUGGACUGACCACCUGCACCUUAGAAUAGAGCGGAUGCACUGGCCGGGGAGCGGGCAGCAGCUGCCCCGCUCCAUCUGCAGCCUGCCCUGCCAACCGGGUGAGCGGAAGAAGACAGUGAAGGGCAUGCCUUGCUGCUGGCACUGCGAGCCUUGCACAGGGUACCAGUACCAGGUGGACCGCUACACCUGUAAGACGUGUCCCUAUGACAUGCGGCCCACAGAGAACCGCACGGGCUGCCGGCCCAUCCCCAUCAUCAAGCUUGAGUGGGGCUCGCCCUGGGCCGUGCUGCCCCUCUUCCUGGCCGUGGUGGGCAUCGCUGCCACGUUGUUCGUGGUGAUCACCUUUGUGCGCUACAACGACACGCCCAUCGUCAAGGCCUCGGGCCGUGAACUGAGCUACGUGCUGCUGGCAGGCAUCUUCCUGUGCUAUGCCACCACCUUCCUCAUGAUCGCUGAGCCCGACCUUGGCACCUGCUCGCUGCGCCGAAUCUUCCUGGGACUAGGGAUGAGCAUCAGCUAUGCAGCCCUGCUCACCAAGACCAACCGCAUCUACCGCAUCUUCGAGCAGGGCAAGCGCUCGGUCAGUGCCCCACGCUUCAUCAGCCCCGCCUCACAGCUGGCCAUCACCUUCAGCCUCAUCUCGCUGCAGCUGCUGGGCAUCUGUGUGUGGUUUGUGGUGGACCCCUCCCACUCGGUGGUGGACUUCCAGGACCAGCGGACACUCGACCCCCGCUUCGCCAGGGGUGUGCUCAAGUGUGACAUCUCGGACCUGUCGCUCAUCUGCCUGCUGGGCUACAGCAUGCUGCUCAUGGUCACGUGCACCGUGUAUGCCAUCAAGACACGCGGCGUGCCCGAGACCUUCAAUGAGGCCAAGCCCAUUGGCUUCACCAUGUACACCACUUGCAUCGUCUGGCUGGCCUUCAUCCCCAUCUUCUUUGGCACCUCGCAGUCGGCCGACAAGCUGUACAUCCAGACGACGACGCUGACGGUCUCGGUGAGUCUGAGCGCCUCGGUGUCCCUGGGAAUGCUCUACAUGCCCAAAGUCUACAUCAUCCUCUUCCACCCGGAGCAGAACGUGCCCAAGCGCAAGCGCAGCCUCAAAGCCGUCGUUACGGCGGCCACCAUGUCCAACAAGUUCACGCAGAAGGGCAACUUCCGGCCCAACGGAGAGGCCAAGUCUGAGCUCUGCGAGAACCUUGAGGCCCCAGCGCUGGCCACCAAACAGACUUACGUCACUUACACCAACCAUGCAAUCUAGCGAGUCCAUGGAGCUGAGCAGCAGGAGGAGGAGCCGUGACCCUGUGGAAGGUGCGUCGGGCCAGGGCCACACCCAAGGGCCCAGCUGUCUUGCCUGCCCGUGGGCACCCACGGACGUGGCUUGGUGCUGAGGAUAGCAGAGCCCCCAGCCAUCACUGCUGGCAGCCUGGGCAAACCGGGUGAGCAACAGGAGGACGAGGGGCCGGGGCGGUGCCAGGCUACCACAAGAACCUGCGUCUUGGACCAUUGCCCCUCCCGGCCCCAAACCACAGGGGCUCAGGUCGUGUGGGCCCCAGUGCUAGAUCUCUCCCUCCCUUCGUCUCUGUCUGUGCUGUUGGCGACCCCUCUGUCUGUCUCCAGCCCUGUCUUUCUGUUCUCUUAUCUCUUUGUUUCACCUUUUCCCUCUCUGGCGUCCCCGGCUGCUUGUACUCUUGGCCUUUUCUGUGUCUCCUUUCUGGCUCUUGCCUCCGCCUCUCUCUCUCAUCCUCUUUGUCCUCAGCUCCUCCUGCUUUCUUGGGUCCCACCAGUGUCACUUUUCUGCCGUUUUCUUUCCUGUUCUCCUCUGCUUCAUUCUCGUCCAGCCAUUGCUCCCCUCUCCCUGCCACCCUUCCCCAGUUCACCAAACCUUACAUGUUGCAAAAGAGAAAAAAGGAAAAAAAAUCAAAACACAAAAAAGCCAAAACGAAAACAAAUCUCGAGUGUGUUGCCAAGUGCUGCGUCCUCCUGGUGGCCUCUGUGUGUGUCCCUGUGGCCCGCAGCCUGCCCGCCUGCCCCGCCCAUCUGCCGUGUGUCUUGCCCGCCUGCCCCGCCCGUCUGCCGUCUGUCUUGCCCGCCUGCCCGCCUGCCCCUCCUGCCGACCACACGGAGUUCAGUGCCUGGGUGUUUGGUGAUGGUUAUUGACGACAAUGUGUAGCGCAUGAUUGUUUUUAUACCAAGAACAUUUCUAAUAAAAAUAAACACAUGGUUUUGCACCCGGGCUCCACAUCCACUGAGGGUCCUGCCAUGGGACCACAGGCUCAGCCUGCAGCUGGAGGGCUUAGACCUAGAGGGAAGCGGGAACUGGGCUCUGGAGACCCAGGGCUUGGGGGCUGUGGAGACUGCUCCCUAGGCUGGGAUCUAGUGUGGUGUGGUGAGGCCUUGGGCAUGGAGGGGCCAGAUUCCCAGGUAAGGGGCAGGGACAUUGCAGGAAAUUCCAGGAAUCAGCACCUAGUAGUCCCCUAAUUAGGGGGUAUGCUCUGUCCCCUGCCCUGCAGCCCUGGGAGGGUAACAUUUCUGCCUUGCCUGUCCUCUGUCUCACACCCCUCACACCUGGGACUGCCCUUCCACCCCUGCCCCCAUAACCUGUGCCUCUCUCCUUCCAGCCAGGAAGUCCUCUUCUUGAGAAGUUAGCUUCCCGGGCUGCCAGCACUCAUAGCCGUCCCCUCCUGCUUGUGUUGGCUCCAGGCUCGGGUGCUAAGAAGAUGUGUGUCUGUCCUGGAGAUCAGUGUGUUGUUAUGUGUCCACGUGGGCCCACAAGUGCACGGCACAGGCAUGGCCGUGUGGCUGUGUUGGCUGUGUUGGCUGUGUGUCUGUGUGCACGUCCAGCGCCUCCAUGCGCAUGCGUGCCUGUCUUGUUUGCGUGUCUGAUCAUCUGUUUGGGCCCCGGUGGCUCAUGCAGAUGCCUGUCUCAGGCCCAUGGCGAGUGUUCACCUCAGCUGGCUUCCCUGGCAGGUUGGGAGGUGGGAAACAGGAGCGCUUAGGGGCUGGGCUCUGGCUGGGGUAAAUUAUAGAGCCAGAAACACAAUGAGGCCAUAGGCAGCAGCUGGAGCCUGGGCUGCCUGUGCCGUCCCCUCCUGCCCUGCCCCUGGGUCCUGCACCCCCUCCCACCUCCAGGCUAGCUGACAGCGCUAUGGAGCACAGUGGAAGGGACUGGAGGAACCCUAGGCAGGGGGCCACGCAGGGACAGAGUAUGAGAGUGUGUGUAUAACUGAGGCUGGGACAUUGAAUCAUGCCAGGUAUGUCUUCUCCAUCAGCCCACUCUUACUCCUGGCCUGGGCAUCUCACACAUCUGUGCAUAGGAAAUCUCUUCUUCCCUGGGGUCUGUGUGCAGCACCUAGUAGAUGCUCAAUAAAUGUUUGUGUGAGGGAAGGAGACAGGAAAGGAAGUGUCUCGCUGAUCAUCUUGCGGAAUGGUUCCUAAGACCUCUGCCCAGGAAAGAUUCCACCCAGUGCUCCAGCCCGGUCAGGCAGAACUAGGUUGCCAGAUCAAGGGUAUCUCCCAAAAGCUUCCAGGGCAGUUGGGGGUGGGGGGGUGGGGGGUAGGGAUGGGGAAUGCAGAAGCGGGUGCAGCCAGCUCUCCCCCAGGGUGACUCUGGCAGCACCCCCAUCCUGGGCACCCUGCCUGCUCUGUGGCUCACGCCCCUCCUGAAGUGACUGAUGCUCUGAGGCCCAAGGCUAGGUCCAGGGCAGGGCCUGCAGGGGUUUCAUGCUCAGUCCAGGACUUGCCUAGGUCCCCCUACAUCUGUGGGGCCCCCAUCUAGGUUCUAACAGGAGAAUCACCUCUCCAAGGGGGAUGCUGCCCCUCGGCUCCCCUUGGCUCUCAGGAGGGGCCCUCAGGGACUACCAGUCCCCUGCCAGUGGGAAGAAAUAGCCCUGCCCUCAGGGAGCUUCCAGUGUGAUGGGGGAGAUACAGCAGACUGUGUCCCAAAGUAAAAUGACUGUUAGAAUGAGGUGGGUGGAGGAGGGAAGCCUUGGGUGGGUGUGACUUUGGGCAUCUGAGCCUGGGGUGCAGAGGUGGGCUCUGUGGGCCUGAGGUGGACAGGAGGGAACCAGGCCCUAGCAAGACUUUUGCCAGCUAGACCUGCUGCAGCAGUUGGGAGGGUGGGUGCUGCUGGAGUCCUGGGUCCAUCACCUAGAAGGCUCAGGCCAGUGCAGCCAGGGCUGGGGCCCACAGCUGGCCUGGGUGGGACCUGCCCUGAUGCCCAUGGCAGGAGGGACGCCUGGCCCUUCACAAUUGGCUUGGCUGCUCACCUUUGCUCUCAUCCUCAAUUAUUAAUGACUGGAGAAAGCUGCUAAGUAUCUUCAGAAUGUUAGAUUUCAACAAGAUGGGGGGUUCAGGGUCCCUGGCACCCUGGAUAGGGAGCCAGCGGCCCCUAGAGACCUUUGCUGUGUGCAGGGGGUAUGUGCUCACCCCCGUGGCCUCAGCCUCCUCAAUGUCUGAAUGAAGGAUUGGGCUAGCAGACAUCCCACCCCACAGCACACUUUCUAACCAGCAGGGGAACUUCUAGACAAUAGAGACGCUGGGCUCCCUCCAGAACACUGGACCUGAACUUCUGGGGGGAGGGCUGGGCACGGGCAUAUUUUAAAAGCUCCCCAGCAGAUGGGCCGUGCAGUCAAGUGGGCCAAGAGUGGCACCAGACUUUGGGGCUUGUGAAGUCAGGAGGGAGCAACAGUGCCCACUCGAGCUUGCCUGGGGCUCAAGCCCAAGGCUGGGCUGCUGCCAGCCUGAGCAGACACCCAGGAGCUUCCAGGCCAGCUGGAUGCACAGGGCACCUUUGUGGAACUCCUAGGACCCUGGGGAGACCCACCUCAGGAGCAGAGUCUCAGGUCCCUUCCGGCUCUGAGGGGCUGUUCUGAGCUCUAAUGUCUUAUGGUCUGCCCCUCCCAUCCUUACUUCUCAGGCCCUGGAGGCAGAGGCAUAGAGCCAGGCAGGACAGAGGUCUCAGUGGGCCACAUGCCAGCUGCCCCCACACUGCCUCAGCCUCCAGGCCUCCAAGGGGUCCUGGGGAGCCCCUGAGAAGAUGCUGAGCCUGCAUAAGGCUGGGCGCCCCUCUUUCUGACACCCUCACUGGCUCCACGGCUCCCCCUUCCCAUCCCAGGUUUCCAUCUGCCCACUGAACAGGGAGGGGAAACUGAGGCACUCCCCUGGCACUGAGGGCUCCUUCUGUCAUCCUGCCUGCCCUGGAUGGUCCUGGCUGCCCCUCAGGGCUUGGCCCUGGCACUGUGAGCCUCACAGGGCUCAGACCCCCACCCCCAACCCAGCACUAAAUGGCACUCGGCACCAGAAUCUCACUUCAGUUGGCAAAAGCAGCAAUUAGCAUGUAAUGAGGCUUCUUGCUUUAUUUUUAGGUAACCUCCAAGGCCCUGCCUGUGUAAUUCAGCCCGCCAUUGCUCGGUGGAUAAUUAAAGCAUGUCACCAUAA